AGUGGCAGCGACAGGCGCCGCCGGGACGGGCACGGGCGCGCGGGCUCCGGCGGGCGCCGGCUGCCUUCCUCCGUCGCUCGCUGUCUCUCCCGGCCGCAUUCUCCUCCGCUGCGGGGCCGAGCUCUCCCCAGCGCUCGCAGGAAGGAAGAAGGGAGCCGAGGACGCCGAGAAGUUCCCGCGGCAGCCGCGGAUCCCGGCCAAGGCGGAGGCUGCGGCUCCGACGGGGCAGGAGCGCGAUCCACGGCGAGGGGCGUACGGCCAAAGGGUCCGCGGCGUGGAGCGCUCGGACCUUCCGCUCUCCCCCGGGCGUGGGCCGGGACCCCAUGAGACGCGCCCACGAGGGGCGCGAGAUUCCUAGCUUGGGCGGCGCUAGGCGGAGGGAGGUGUUGCAGCCGCCGGAGCCAGAGAGCUGCCGGCAGGAGGCGGCGGCGGCAAGAACUUGAACUUGGCGUCGGGAGCGGGCGCCCCGGACGCCCCCCGCCGGGGCCGGGGCGCCGAGGGACCUGCGCCGCAGCGCUGCCCCCCGAAUGGCCGCGGCGGCGGACCGGGCUCCCGCGCCGCGGCCCUAGGCGGCCUCUCGCCAUGGCCAAGUGGCUAAACAAGUACUUCAGCUUGGGCAACAGCAAGACCAAGAGCCCCCCGCAGCCGCCGCGGCCAGACUACCGCGAGCAGCGGCGCCGAGGCGAGCGGCCUUCGCAGCCCCCCCAGGCCGUGCCGCAGGCCUCCUCCGCCGCCUCGGCGUCCUGCGGUCCGGCCACCGCCUCCUGCUUCUCAGCCUCUUCGGGCUCGCUGCCCGACGACAGCGGCAGCACCAGCGACCUCAUCCGCGCCUACCGCGCGCAGAAGGAGCGAGACUUCGAGGACCCCUACAACGGGCCUGGCUCGUCGCUGCGCAAACUGCGCGCCAUGUGCCGCCUGGACUACUGCGGCGGCAGCGGGGAGCCAGGCGGGGUCCAGCGCGCCUUCUCGGCCUCGUCCGCGUCGGGCGCCGCGGGCUGUUGCUGCGCCUCCUCGGGCGCGGGGGCCGCCGCGUCCUCGUCCUCGUCCUCCGGCUCUCCGCAUCUCUACCGCAGCAGCAGCGAGCGGCGGCCCGCCACGCCGGCCGAGGUGCGCUACAUCUCCCCCAAGCACCGCCUCAUCAAAGUGGAGAGCGCCGCGGGCGGUGGGGCCGGGGACCCCCUGGGGGGCGCCUGCGCGGGCGGCCGCACCUGGAGCCCGACGGCCUGCGGAGGCAAGAAACUGCUCAACAAGUGCGCCGCCUCAGCCGCGGAGGAGAGCGGGGCCGGCAAGAAGGACAAGGUGACCAUAGCCGAUGACUACUCAGAUCCCUUUGAUGCCAAGAAUGAUCUCAAGAGCAAAGCAGGAAAGGGGGAGAGUGCUGGCUACAUGGAGCCCUAUGAGGCACAGAGGAUCAUGACAGAAUUUCAGAGGCAGGAAAGUGUCCGGUCCCAGCAUAAAGGUAUCCAGUUAUAUGACACCCCUUACGAACCUGAAGGCCAAAGUGUUGACUCAGACUCGGAGAGCACAGUCAGCCCCCGACUGCGGGAGAGCAAGCUGCCCCAGGAUGACGACAGGCCCGCCGAUGAGUACGACCAGCCUUGGGAGUGGAACCGGGUCACCAUCCCAGCCCUGGCAGCACAGUUUAAUGGCAACGAGAAGCGGCAGUCAUCCCCCUCACCUUCGCGGGACCGGCGGCGCCAGCUUCGUGCCCCUGGAGGGGGCUUUAAGCCUAUCAAACAUGGGAGCCCUGAGUUCUGCGGGAUCCUAGGAGAAAGGGUGGAUCCUGCCGUCCCCCUGGAGAAGCAAAUAUGGUAUCACGGAGCCAUCAGCAGAGGAGACGCCGAGAACCUGCUGCGACUCUGCAAGGAGUGUAGCUACCUUGUCCGGAACAGCCAGACCAGCAAGCAUGACUACUCCCUCUCCCUGAGGAGCAACCAGGGUUUUAUGCACAUGAAACUGGCCAAAACCAAAGAGAAAUACGUUCUGGGUCAGAACAGCCCUCCGUUCGACAGUGUCCCGGAAGUCAUCCACUACUACACCACCAGAAAGCUACCCAUCAAAGGGGCUGAGCACUUGUCCCUCCUCUAUCCCGUGGCUGUGAGGACCCUGUGAGCGGACCAGACCUGCCCUGCUCUGUGACAGAGCCUGAGACUUGGAGGUGCCAGAGGCCCCCCACCAACCAGCCCAGCCACUGUUGCUGGCUGUGUCGUUUGUGUUGUGUGUAUGGUACUAGCACACCACUGCAUGUCUCUAGAAUGCUGUUGCCACUUACGGGGGCUGGAGAAGGCCUGGAUAAAGACAGAAGGGCGGCAACACACCACCCCAGCCCCCACCCCCACCCUCUCCUUGAGUUUCUGUGAAUUAAAAUAUUUGCAAAUCCAAAGAGAUGCCUUCCAGGAUGAACAAAGGCAGACCAGCUCCGAGGGGCGGGGUAGGGUGGGGCGGGAGCUCCCUGGCUGACAUCUCUUUGUUCUCCAGCUGUCUCAAAUUCACACCUCUGUACAGGGCAAAGUUUUCCCACAGGAGCCCCCCUACUGAUGCUGGGAGCCAAAUGCUGGUGCUUUGAGAGUCCCGGAGGCCCCGGGGUUCCCGCCCCGCUGGUGUGUAUAUGUGUGUCUGUGUGAGUGUGUGUGUGAGUACAGAUGUGAGAAGGUGGUCACACACAGAUGGGUAAGCCCACUGAUCUACUUGUAGUCACUCAGUGUAAUCAUUAGGCUAUCUUCAAGGAAUCAUUGUGCAGUCAAAAAGAGGAUUCAAUUAUUUAUGAAUAGGGUGUGUAAAUAAAAUAGUCAUUUAAUAUAUAGCCUUAUCCUUUUUUGAUAUACUGCAGAGGGUCUCUGAGGGGGCAGUUCUGGUUUCACUCCCAGAGCAAGGCGUGUCUCCUCUGGGCUUGCUGCUGUGGCAGGCCCCAGGGAGGGGAGGGAGGCCGAGGCCUCAGCUCCAGCCCUCAGCAGCUCUGGACACAAGAGCCGUCUGCUCUGACAACUGGGCUGAGGCAGUCGGUAGCACUCUGGGAGUCAACCCAGAGCUCAGAGUUCAGGCUUCAGCAGUGGACAUAGUCAGGAGCCUCCAGUGUUGACCAAAAAACCAGUCUUUCCCUCCUGCAGUGGGACGUCUGUGUUGACACCCCCCCAACCCCUGGACACAGCACCCAGCUGGCUACAAAGGGCUCUCUCCCCACUAUCUGUUAGCACCACCUGGGAGGUAUUUGGCAUGUAGGGAAAGGGAGACAGAGAAGGAACGUCAUUUGCCCAAAGCCACACAGCUCACCAGCAGCAGAGCGGUUCUGCAGCCAAUGCUCUUUCGUUGGUUCUGCAUGGCCUUGCUGUCACCCUGCCCAUGGAGGAGGGAGAAUCCUGACCUCCCAGGGACAUAGAGCCCUCAGUGGUCCACACUGCUUCCACACACAAGAACACCUACACACACACACACACACACACACACAGCCCUCAGUGGUCCACACUGCUUCCACACACAAGAACACCUACACACACACACACACACACACACAGCCCUCAGUGGUCCACACUGCUUCCACACACAAGAACACCUACACACGCACACGCACACGCGACCUCUCUCUUGCUUGCCAUAGCAGGGUCCUCCCACACAGGCCAGGCAGCCCCGAUGAGGCUAAGAGUUUCUCAGCUCUCCUGCUUUUUCCACCCACCCAGUAGCAUGAAGAUGUGGCUGCCCUCUCCUGAAUGAGAUACAAGGGUUCCAGAGCCUUCGCCAGGCACCAGCUGGUCUGAAUGAACUAGAAGUUUGACGACUGUCAUCCCUGGCCCACCUGGGCAGAGCACAAGGGGCCGAGUUUGAAUGUCAUCAGCAGGUUCAGACAUCAGCGCUGCUCAUGUCUUUAGAGACUGUUUGGAGGUGGUUCCAGCUCACUGUUCACAUGCAGAGACACAGGCCCGGAGAAGGAGGACUCGCCAAGGCCACGUGUCGAGCUGGGACUGAGCCCUGCCCCUUUAGGUAGCUGCGUGGACUUCAGCGGUUUGUGCAAAGCCCUGCCCUUGGUGACCCGCCUUUAGUGACCAGUCUGCCUCUUGGGUCUUCCUCCCAGGCCUUGUCUGGCACGUCCACGUGGCCCAGCCCUCAUAGAGACCACGCUGGCUGUGGCCUGGGUUUAAUCUCUUAAAGAAGCCAAUCCUUUCCUUGCCUGUUUGGCAUUUCCUAAAACAUCCCUCAAUGAGGGAGGAAGGCAGGGACACCCUGGAACGAUUCGUGCUUUCCUUUGGGGGAGUGGGAAGGUAGGUGGGAAAUGACAAGAUGAGUGAGGAGUUGGCACUUGGCCAAACAGAGGAGCCUGGACCCCAAGGCUUAUUCUCAGAGGAGGCCCAAGAGAGGCUGAGGAAGAGGGGGAACAACCCUCCGGCGGGGGAGGAGGGUGAGACCUCACACUGGCAAGUUCAGGUCCAGCCACUUCCUGAGGCUGCUGGGUGGGGCCGCACCUCACGGUCCUUCCCUGUAGACCAUCUUCCCGGGCACAUUGCUCCUCAGAAAAGGCUCUGGGAGGGUCUCAGUGGAAGCUGGCAGCUGUGCCCUCUGGCCCUGACUUGGCCUCUUAGGGUAUUCCUGGGACCCUCCCUCUGUCCCUGGCCUUCGUCUUCCUGAAGUUUCCCUGGGAGGCCCAACCUCCUGCCCCUCUCAGGGACAGAGGCCAGCAGAGGAGCCAGCUUACAGGAUGGGAGCUGCUGAAAAGAAUUUUUUUCCCUUAAUUUUAUGAACCUCUCCCUCUUCUUCCUCUAAUUGUGACCGUUUCCUGUGUCAGCCUGUAUUCAUGUUUUCUUGGACAUCUAACAAUUGAAACAGCUUUUCCCUUUCAGAAACACUCACAUUCAGGUUACUGGCUUUGGUUUGGUUUUUGUUUUGGGUUUGUUUUUUUUUUUUUUCAUCUGCUGCCAAUUAAUUGGGGAAAAAAUUGAGCUGGAUUUCUUUGAGAGAAAAGAAAAGCUCCUGCCACACAACGUCGCGCCCUCGGCAUUUUGUCUGAGAACCUCCAGCACUAGCGGCUGUUUCUGUGUCUCCCUUCUUUGCUGGCUUUAUUAUUGACCAUAAUGCCUGCCCACUUGAGCAACUCUGUCCUUGAGCGCUGAGGAGUCAAGGGCCCUUCUGGCAGCCCCCCAAACAGGAUGGCGCCCACAGAAAGAAAGGAGGCUUUGUAGGGGAAGAGGGCCCCACCGCCUGCCAGUCCCGUCCUGAAGUCAGAAGAAUGGCCCAGGCUGACACCCUCUCCUGGAGAGAGGCUCACAGCGUAGCUGUUCCCAGGAAAGGGGUGCAAAGACUCCGAGGCUUCAGGAGGCAGGCCCUGUCCUCACAGGGCGGCUGUGGGCCGGGGCCCCUCUGUGGCCUGAGAGUGAGCAGGAGGGAAACCUGAAGCAGCUACCCGCAAGGCGUCCGGUCAACAGGGUGGAGCUGCAGGCUCCCUCUGCCCAUUCCCAGAACCAGCGGCCCCCUUUGUAAGAUGCUGAACACGAAGUUCCGGUAGCUCCCCAGACGCUGUCUCAGAAGUGGUGAUAUCAUUGACCAAGGGCCUGGCAAGGACCGGCAGCCAGGGUCCCCAUUUGCUCUUGCAGCCCUAGGGACUGUGCAGGUAGAAGCCCUGCCAGCAGAGCAGGCUGGCGUUUGGUGUUGGCCCACAGACACCCGUGAAGGGUCAUGGCCGAAUCAGGCAGCUGUCCAGCCAACUGUCUCUCCACCCUUCCAGAAUUGGUGAUCAGCGAAGACCAAAUUCGGCAAGCCAUCCAGAGGGAGUGCAGGGCGCACAGUCUUAGAUGUGGGCGCACCUCCCAGAACCCCACGGGGACUUGUUCACAGGCGCGCUUGCAGGAGGGCAAGCCCCUUGGUCCUGGAACACAGGUGCCCCUUGGCCUUUCCACCUCCCUCCUUGGGGCUGUUUGCAUCCCUGCCAGGAGCCUUAAACCAGCCACCUACUGCUGAAGUCUCUUGUAACAUUCCAAAUCUAUGUGACACACUGUAUAAUGAUGAAUAUUUAAUGUGAAGCUCUUAAUAUACUACAAGUGUCUUGUUUA